CUCUGGGACGCCCCUCCGGACCGGUUUCGCCUCGCGGAGCCGGUAGGUCCAGGUGCAGCGGCCGCAGUGCUGCGUCCGUGCGCCGCGGGCUGGGGCGGUCUCAGGUGUGCCGAAGCUCUGGUCAGUGCCAUGAUCCGGCAGGAGCGCUCCACAUCCUACCAGGAGGCUGUGCGUCCAGCGCUUCCUUCAAGCAAGCCCUGCCUCCUCACUUCUCCAGCUGUAUUAGUGAAACUGCUCUCCUCCUCCGCCUCCACUUCUCGGCCCCCAAACCUUGGUCAUCUUUGGCAACCGUCCUCUUCUGUGCCCCUCCAUCGUGCCGCCUCAUUGGCCAAAGUCAGGCAGUUCCAGCUGAGUGAGGAGUUGGUCCAGGUGGUUGAGAACUCAGAGCUGGCAGACGAGCAGGACAAGGAGACGGUCAGAGUCCAAGGUCCGGGUAUCUUACCAGGCCUGGACAGCGAGUCCGCCUCCAGCAGCAUCCGCUUCAGCAAGGCCUGCCUGAAGAACGUCUUCUCGGUCCUACUCAUCUUCAUCUACCUGCUGCUCAUGGCUGUGGCCGUCUUCCUGGUCUACCGGACCAUCACAGACUUUCGUGAGAAACUCAAGCACCCUGUCAUGUCUGUGUCUUACAAGGAAGUGGAUCGCUAUGAUGCCCCAGGUAUUGCCUUGUACCCCGGUCAGGCCCAGUUGCUCAGCUGUAAGCACCAUUACGAGGUCAUUCCUCCUCUGACAAGCCCUGGCCAGCCGGGUGACAUGAAUUGCACCACCCAGAGGAUCAACUACACGGACCCCUUCUCCAAUCAGACUGUGAAAUCUGCCCUGAUUGUCCAGGGGCCCCGGGAAGUGAAAAAGCGGGAGCUGGUCUUCCUCCAGUUCCGCCUGAACAAGAGUAGUGAGGACUUCAGCGCCAUUGAUUACCUCCUCUUCUCUUCUUUCCAGGAGUUCCUGCAAAGCCCAAACAGGGUAGGCUUCAUGCAGGCCUGUGAGAGUGCCUAUUCCAGCUGGAAGUUCUCUGGGGGCUUCCGCACCUGGGUCAAGAUGUCACUGGUAAAGACCAAGGAGGAGGAUGGGCGGGAAGCAGUGGAGUUCCGGCAGGAGACAAGUGUGGUUAACUACAUUGACCAGAGGCCAGCUGCCAAAAAAAGUGCUCAAUUGUUUUUUGUGGUCUUUGAAUGGAAAGAUCCUUUCAUCCAGAAAGUCCAAGAUAUAGUCACUGCCAAUCCUUGGAACACAAUUGCUCUUCUCUGUGGCGCCUUCUUGGCAUUAUUUAAAGCAGCAGAGUUUGCCAAACUGAGUAUAAAAUGGAUGAUCAAAAUUAGAAAGAGAUACCUUAAAAGAAGAGGUCAGGCAACGAGCCACAUAAGCUGAAGUCACCUCGCGUUGUUUAGAGAACUGUCCACAUCAAUGGGAGCUGUCAUCACUUCCACUUUGUAAACGGAGCUAUCAACAAUCCUGUACUCACUUGAAGAAAUGGGGCCUUGCUGGGAGGAACAGCAUGUAAAACUGGAACUUCUAACCCCGUCCCAAAAGAGGCGGUGUAGAGCCUAAUAGAAGAGACUAAUGGAUAAACCUACAAGUUAUUUAAAUAUUUAAAUUAUUAAUAAACUUUUUAAAGAGCUGGCCAAUGACUUUUGAAUAGGGUUUGUAGAAGAUGCCUUUCUUCCUGUUUGGUUCAUUGUAUUGUAUUAGGUUAAGCUCUACUAGGGUAAUGAAGGCUCUACUUUUCACUUUUUAAAAGUGGACAAAAGAGUGUGAUUUUCUUUUUCCAAAAAUUCCUGAGUAUCAAGACGUGCAGGUCAUGCUUUGGAGCCUAUGCACUGUACACAAAGGCAAAACCCUAUGACUUUGGCAUCAUCUGCCAUUGAUGUCCAGCCUCUGACAUGCUCUUUGAUUUGUUAAAUGUUAAAUGAGACUUUAAGGCUACUAGAAACUAGUAAUUAAGUUUCUUAAUGGACUGAGUAGCCACCUACUUGUCCGGCUAGAAUGUUUGUUGAUGUAUGAGUUUAGAUUAACACUCAAAAGCACUAGGACAGAUGUACAUAGAAGGUGCCUACUCAUUGUAUUUUGAUGAUUUCAUUAACAGGUAAAUAAAAGUUAAUACAAAAGGAACGAGUGUGACAAUAUGAAUAUCUGCUCAAUCAUCGGGCACAAUUACUUUCAUUUGGUGACUUCCAAGGACAAAAAGGUAGUAUGAGUCUGGACUCCCAAGAUGGAUCUGACUCCCAAGGUAUGUUCUAACUGCUUCCAGGGAAGGGUUUGUUAGGCAUGGCAACUGAUGGCAGGUGUCCAGAAAGAGUGACCUGGUGUCCCCGAGGAAGCUGGGUUAACUCUUUACUGUGUCCACAAAACUACCCAUCAUAUGAGGAAGGGGCAUACGCAGUGUGACCCUCAAAAAGCUUUUAGCCUAGCCUUUGACAGAAAUGAGUAUGCAUUAAAAAAAAGUCUAUUUUUCACAUUAAGGUUCUAAAAAUUGUUUCCAGAGUUUUAAAUUAUUUAUGUGCCUGUUGCUUCAAAGAGGACUUGGUAGCAUUUCCUAAAUUUUGUAAUCUGGCUUCCGAUAAUCCAAAGGGAAUAACUCAAAUGUAUGAAUAGGCAUUUUAAAUGGGAAGAAACUGUUUUUUGGAUGAAUGAUUAAAAGUGAACUGUAUAAAGAAA